GAUAGCAUUUUAACUGGAUAGCUGACUGGCUGAUUUUAUAUUCCCACUUAAUGGAUAGAGAAAUUGAGGCAUUAGGAACCAUAUGGACCUGCCUUACUCUGAGAGGGAAAUAGGAGCAGGCCUGGGAAGUUUUCCCAGGAAAGAGAAUUUGUUAUAGCUUCAUAGAUUCAUGGGAUGCAUGAAUUUUCUUUUUCUUUUUUUUUGAGUUGCAAGAUUGUGAGGUUGCAGAUGCUCUGUGUAAAACAAUGCCCCACAGGGAGGGAAGUGUGAGGUCCGGCCUGAGGCCACCCUUAAAAAGGGCUAUAAACAGCAGCUGCUUCUAUUGUGCGUGCCAAGUGCUGCCUAUUAGUUUAGGUUUCCAAACUCCUUGUUUCUUUCUCUUGAACCAGAUGUGACCGAGCAAGAGUUUGUCAAUUCAGAGGUAGACCCCAGAUGGUGGGAAUCAAAGGAGGGAAGUGAGGGGCACACGGGCCUCUGGGGGCUGAGGCAGGAGACAGCUCUCUGCCUUUCUCAGGUAGAGGACCUUUGGAGAUGUGAAUGAAAACAGCUGUCUGAACAAGUGGUACCCUAACUAGCGCGGCUGGCCUAAUCAAGGGAAUGGAAGAUGAGGAGAAUGAAGGCUCUGGGAAUUUAUUUUCAUCGUGGACCGGACUUUUUAUCAGCCAGGAAAAAGGCAGUUUUCUUAGCUGUGAUUCCCACUGCUGCCAUUGUCUGUGCAAUCACAUCCAGAAGAAGGGUCACGGUUACAUGGAUCUGCUGGGAAAACAAUUAGUGGAAAAGGGGGCAAAUAGAGUUAAUGGCCGUUUUUGGUAAGCAAUGGCCUCAGUUUUGCUUCUGUUUUGGAUGAACACCACCACAUAGGGCCUGAAUGUGAAAGAAGACCCUCUAUUUGUCUGUUCCGGGGCAGCCUGGUAGUAAAACACUGUUGAAUGGGCCACAGUUUCAGCAGACCAUCAGGUGAAUGGGACCAGUCUCUCUUCUUCCAAAAUAUCAGAAGUUAAACACUUGGAACGGAGAUUUGGCCAAGAUGACCCAUUUACAGGCUGGACUCAGUCCAGAGACUAUAGAGAAAGCUCGCCUGGAACUGAAUGAAAACCCCGAUGUUUUACAUCAGGAUAUUCAGCAAGUCAGGGACAUGAUCAUCACCAGGCCUGACAUUGGAUUUUUACGUACAGAUGAUGCCUUCAUCCUGAGAUUUCUCCGAGCCAGGAAGUUUCACCAAGCGGAUGCCUUUAGACUCCUGGCUCAGUAUUUCCAGUACCGCCAGCUAAACCUGGACAUGUUCAAAAACUUCAAGGCAGAUGAUCCCGGCAUUAAGAGGGCUCUGAUCGAUGGGUUCCCCGGGGUGCUGGAAAACCGAGACCAUUACGGCAGGAAGAUUCUUUUGCUGUUUGCAGCCAAUUGGGAUCAGAGUAGGAACUCCUUCACAGACAUCCUUCGUGCCAUCCUGCUGUCAUUGGAAGUCCUAAUCGAAGAUCCGGAGCUUCAGAUAAAUGGCUUCAUUUUAAUUAUAGACUGGAGUAAUUUUUCCUUCAAACAAGCCUCCAAACUGACACCUUCAAUCCUUAAACUGGCCAUUGAAGGGUUGCAGGACAGCUUUCCUGCCCGCUUUGGAGGAGUCCACUUUGUCAACCAGCCCUGGUACAUUCAUGCCCUCUACACACUCAUCAAGCCAUUUCUUAAAGACAAGACCAGGAAACGGAUUUUCCUGCAUGGAAACAAUUUAAACAGCCUUCACCAGCUAAUACACCCUGAAUUUUUGCCCUCUGAAUUUGGAGGAACUCUUCCUCCUUAUGACAUGGGAACUUGGGCCCGGACGUUACUCGGUCCCGACUACAGCGAUGAAAAUGACUAUACUCACACAUCCUAUAAUGCAAUGCACGUGAAGCAUACGUCCUCGAAUCUGGAGAGAGAAUGCUCACCCAAGCUGAUGAAAAGAUCUCAGUCUGUGGUAGAAGCUGGGACCCUGAAACAUGAGGAGAAGGGAGAGAAUGAGAACACCCAGCCACUCCUGGCUCUGGACUGAACCCUGAGUCACCCCAAUGCUCCUGCACACUGGCCUUCAGUGGUAUCAGCCACCCAGGAAGCACAUGCACAACUGACCCAUGCAGACACGUGUGUUCUGCUUGACACAAGGUCCUCCACUCCUGAACCCCUGCAGUGACUGUCACCAGCCAUCGGUCUGAGCAGCCAAAGUUGGACAAAGACUUGAGAGAUGCUUUUUUUUUCCCCCAGUGAGGGGACUGGAGGAUGAUGCAAGGCAUUUAUGUAAAAAAGAUUCUCCCUCCUUUCAUAUUUAUUGUAGUAAAUUGAAAAAAUAAAGACUAAAUUUGAUGGACACACUGCAUUAGGACAAGAAUUUUUCUGAGGUAUCACACAGGGACCCUCUCCAGUUUUUGAAAAUUAAGUGCAUUUCCAAGUAAAUGUAUCAGAGUUAAACUGUACAGACACCACUGUCAAGUUUCAUGUAGUACAAAGCCCUGAGACAAUAGUAUCUCCAGUAAUUUCCAUUCUUACUGAAUUAUUUCCUUUGACCUCAUCACCAGCAUCGAAUUGUUCAGCCUAAGAGCAUGUUCUCAUAGGUCUGGGUAUUUGCAAAGUUUGCUUAUUUUGAUGAUAUCCUGCAAAAAAUUAUUUUGAUGUCACAUCUCUUGUCAGGUCACUAGCUGACUGUCAUGAGCUGACGUUAAAGGAAGACACAUGGACGUGAAAUACGAUUAUUUCAUCUGAGCAAUGUGAGUUACCACAGGCAGCUCAAAAGCCCAUUAGUGCAGCAUGUGUCUGCAGAGGAGAUGUCUCAUGAAAAUCACAUGUCAGUGAUUAAUGAAUCCAUUCCAGUUGCCUCAACUGGGUCACUACAGCAAAGAAAAGUGCUAUCAAACCAUUUACCCUUGCCCCCACAACCCUCCUGCAACCAUUAAAGAUGUGGAGAAAGACCAUGGUUGUUGCUGAGAGGGUAAAUAUUCAAUCAUGGAGCAUGACCCAUAUGGAUGGCUAAAUAUGCAAGUACUGAAGUAAGAGAAGACUAGAAAUGCAGGAUGAAAUGUCAAAGGUCAUUUUAUUUACCUAGUCUCCUUAGAAAUGGAGUCCCCAACUACUCAUUCAAAAGAAAUCAGACAUAAAAUAAACAGACAUCAUAUAUGAUAUCCUUACUUGUGCCAUGUUUUCCAAGACCAGUGCAUAUUUUUAGACAUCUCUUAUUCGCCCAGCCAUCUGCAUGACAUGGGUAUUUAUUAGUAUUACCAGUUGGUGCUCAAAGUCAAACAAAAAUAUUUUAGUUAAUAAUGGGCAGUAAAAUAUGAUUUUACAUUAUUUUAAAUAUUUGGGAGAGUUAAUUUGUUAGCUAAAUAAUUCAAGGGAAAGAGAUUAUUCAACUGGUCAUAAUCACCCCUGAUAAUAUUAUUACUAAUCUUAAUUAUUUAUUACAUCAUCUCUUUCUCAAUGGAUCUAAUGUUUUAAUUUUUUCCCCUAUUGGUAGAGAACAAUAACAGAAGUAAUUUUUAUAUUAUACACUUGGAGAAAUAAAGUUGAAACAGAAUUAAAAAUAUUUCUCAAACAACUGUAUCACAAUAUAAAUUAAACUAAUUCAUUUUUGUGUAGACAUACGAAAUCACAAAAAUAAUAACACUGAAAUAAUUCUACCAAUGCAGUGAUGGAAACACUUUUCUUAUGUACCAAGACAUAGAUAGGUAAGAGAAAUAAAGAAUUGAAGUGAAUUAGAAAAUCCAUUUUAUUGCUUGGGUUUAAAAUAGUUGUGGGAUACAAGUAUUUACAAUGCUAUUGGAGUCAAUUAUUGACAACACUUUGCAACAGUAAUACCAUUUCUAGCUUUUCAAUUGGCAAUACUUAGAACCUUACUGUAGUGACCUGAUUUUAAAUACCAUAUUAUAUUUACUAAGUUAAGAGCUAGUUUUUACUCUCUUCCAUAAUUUCAUUACAUGAAUGUAAGAUGAUGGCUCAAAAAUGACGACUUAUAGUUUGAAUUUAUGUGUAUGCAAUAUACAUAUGAGAACCAAAUUCAACAAGUGACAUGAAUGUUACUACAUGAACAUUGAAUUGUAUUGCCCUUGUCAGUUAUUUCCUCUGUUCAAUAAAUACUGAAGGUCACAAACA